CACAUCAAAGUCCGGAGACCCCAUGUGCCGCUCCCAGCGACAAGGGACUCGGAGCAGCGACGACUUCAGACUCACCGGCUGGACGGGGACCAGGACUGGGGUGGGGUAGGGAAGUUGCUACUUCCAGGGAACGGCGGCGACCGCUACAGCGCAGGCCGCGGACCCGACCGCGGCAGGCGAAGUGGGGUGGGGGGAGUGGAAAUUAGGGAGGGUGGGGAAGAGGGCAACACGCAAGCGCCAAGGGUCAGGUGCCGCGGUGGAUGCCGGGACACGGAGUCCCCGGUAGAGAAAGAAACUGGCUAAAUGAGAGAAAGCGAACUACCAAUCCCAGGAUGACCCGCGCACGACCUGGCUGUCACGAAGGCCCGGAGGAGGGCGCUUGCGGGCGGGGCACAACGAGAAGCCACCGGAAGCGGAAGCCAGAAUGGCGCCAUUUUGCGGUACGGAAGCUACACAGCAACACGUAUAGGAGACUCUCCCCGAGAUCUUCUAGGGAGUGACCCAUCUAUUUUUGUUUGGGAAGAGGAAACUCCGAAAUGGGAUCGCGGAAGACUUAAAGGGCCAGGCUGAUUUUUUUUUCCUACUGCAGGUCUCUGAGGCUGUGGUUGCUACAGGGUCACCACGAGCUUGGCUUACUUGUCUCAUCCUUCCCUUGCCUGGUAUCAUUUUCUCAGUUCUCCCAAAAGCCAUGUCCCGGCCCUUGCUCAUCACCUUCACCCCAGCCACUGACCCCAGCGACCUCUGGAAGGAUGGGCAGCAGCAGCCACAGCCCGAGAAGCCAGAGUCCACCCUGGAUGGGGCUGCAGCCCUAGCUUUCUAUGAGGCCCUGAUUGGGGAUGAGAGCAGCGCUCCUGACUCCCAGAGAUCUCAGACUGAACCUGCCAGAGAAAGAAAGAGAAAGAAAAGAAGAAUAAUGAAGGCACCAGCAGCAGAAGCAGUGGCAGAAGGAGCAUCAGGAAGACAUGGACAAGGGAGAUCCCUUGAGGCUGAGGAUAAGAUGACUCACCGGAUACUGAGGGCAGCCCAGGAGGGGGACCUGCCAGAACUUAGGAGACUGCUGGAACCGCAUGAGGCAGGAGGAGCUGGGGGGAAUAUCAACGCCCGGGAUGCCUUCUGGUGGACCCCACUGAUGUGUGCUGCUCGAGCGGGCCAGGGGGCAGCUGUGAGCUAUCUCCUGGGCCGUGGGGCUGCCUGGGUGGGGGUCUGUGAGCUGAGUGGCAGGGAUGCGGCUCAGCUCGCUGAAGAAGCUGGCUUCCCUGAGGUAGCCCGCAUGGUCAGGGAGAGCCAUGGAGAGACAAGGAGCCCGGAAAACCGGUCUCCUACUCCCUCCCUCCAGUACUGCGAGAACUGUGACACCCACUUCCAAGAUUCCAACCACCGCACAUCCACUGCUCACCUGCUGUCACUGUCGCAGGGUCCUCAGCCUCCCAACCUUCCACUUGGGGUGCCCAUCUCCAGCCCGGGCUUCAAACUGCUGCUGAGGGGGGGCUGGGAGCCAGGAAUGGGGCUGGGACCCCGGGGUGAGGGCCGUGCCAAUCCCAUCCCCACUGUCCUCAAGAGAGACCAGGAAGGACUAGGCUACAGAUCAGCACCCCAGCCCCGAGUGACACAUUUCCCAGCUUGGGAUACCCGAGCUGUGGCUGGGAGGGAGAGACCCCCUCGGGUGGCCACACUGAGCUGGAGGGAGGAGAGAAGGAGGGAGGAGAAAGACAGGGCUUGGGAGCGGGAUCUAAGGACUUACAUGAACCUCGAGUUCUGACUUUGGUAAAGUCUGACCCUAGUCUGCUGCUGAAGUCUGAACUUGGGCCUCUGACCUGGGCCCUUUGACUUCCCCUUCCUGGGAUCUGCCCAGAUGCAGAUCCUGAAGUUUUUGGUCAAUAGGCUCUGUCUUCGUGAGAGACGGGCUGAGAGUCAGAAAUAAAUCAACCAUUUGUGGUUUAUUCACUUUUCUGGAAGCUAUUUUGAGGAAGCCAAACAGAAGCCUGGGAGCCACAUGCAAGUCCCACCUGAGUCAGAAGGGGCAGCCUCUCCAGGUGGCAUGAUAAGGUCACCUCCCUGCCAAUCUGGGUUCACUUUCAGGUCCCAGACCCUCCUGGGAGUCCCCCACCUAUUCUUUCAACCCCCCUGGACCAAGAAUUGCCCAGCUUCGUGCAAGUCUCACUUCCCCCAGGAGGAGUUCCCUGACUACAGCCAAUUCACUGAUUCACAAACAUAAGUCCAUAUACUAUGUGCCAAGAAUACAGGUAAAGACAUUCCCAACCCUCAAAGAGUUCACAGCUGGAGAGGGAAAGUGCCAUGUUAUCAAUUUUUUUCUUUUUUUUUUUGAGAUGCAGUUUCGCUCUCAUUGCCCAGGCUGGAGUGCAAUGGCAUGAUCUCGGCUCACCACAACCUCUGCCCCCCGAGUUCAAGGGAUUCUCCUGCCUCAGCCUCCCCAGUAGCUGGGAUUACAGGCAUGCCCCACCACGCCCAGCUAAUUUUGUAUUUUUAGUAGAGACGGGGUUUCUCCAUGUUGGCCAAGCUGGUCUUGAACUCCCGACCUCAGGUGAUCCGCCGGCCUCGGCUUCCCAAAGUGCUGGGGUUGCAGGCAUGAGCCACCACUCCCGGCCCAUGUUAUCAAAUAUUAUAAUGCAGGGUGAUAAGGGAAGUCAAGGCCUCUAGAGAUGAGAAUGGGUAGGGUUUUGCUGGAAGAGGCCAGUGUGAUAGGAGGGCCCACGAUUAUCAAGCUUGUACACUUAGUUGAACUGGGACCAGAACUCUAGCCCCCAAAUCUAAACUUUAAGUCAAACUUCUUUGUUCCACCCA